AACCACAUCGCCCGACCGUGCUCUUUAUUUUUCGGUGGAGCAGCUCUGCUUUCUCAGGUCUCUACUUACUUAUAUAAGAUGGCAUCAAGAAGAAGGACCUGACCACUGGCCCCUGACUACAUGGUCUUUGGAACCCGUGGCAUUGGAAGAUGUCAGAGACAUGGCACAUGGAUGUGAUCUUCAAAAACUGUUACAGCCUCAUCUCAUUGGAUUGGUCUACACAUCAAGGUGCUGGAAGUGUCGCAUGCCCAGAGAUGAUGUGGAAGCUCUAUACCCCUUUCCCUUCUGCCCACCUUGCCCUGUGCAUCUCUUCCUGAAUGGCUUCUCCUGAAUUGUAUCCUUUAUAAUAAACUGGUAAAUAGGAAAGAGAUAAUAUCUUCUACUUAAUCCUGGAUACUAUAUCUGAAGUCAGAGCAUCCACUCCAAAGCAGAGAAUUUCUGAAAAACAAAAUAAUGUCAUCAUAUGAUGUUAGAAUUUUUUUUCAAAUGAUGGUUCCUAAUACUUCACAUUAGAAGAACUCGAAUUUGAUGACCAGUUUGAGAAACACCAGUAUAUCCAGAUUACAAGAAAAAGCGAGUCAAAAGGAUGAUCAUGAAUAUAACAACUUCGAGGAAACAUUUAACCAAAGACCAAAGCUUUUUAAACAACUGAGAGUUUUUAUAAGAAAAAGACCUCAUACAGUAGUCCCCACUUAUUCAUGGGGGAUACAUUUCAAGACCCACAGAGAAGGCCUGAAAUCACUGAUGUACCAAACCCUAACCAGGUUCUUAGGAUGAGCUACUAAAUGACAAAUGGGUGGGUAGUACAUAGAGUGUAGAUACACCAGACAAAGAAAUGAUUCACAGCCCAGGCAGGACAGAGCAGAUCACACAAGAUUUCAUCACAGUACUCAGAAAACCACACCAUUUAAAAGUUAUGAAUUGUUUAUUUCUGGAAUUUUCCAUAUAAUAUUUUUGACCACAGUUUCCCAUGGAUAACUGAAACCAUGGGAAGUGGAACUGUGGAUAAGGCAGGACUACUGUAACUAUGACAUCAAUGGUAGGAACCUGAAGCAUAAUUCUGCUGUAGUGGAUUUUUUCAAAAGAAACUCAUGAAUGAAAAAUAAUUUAUUAGAUAUAAGAAAGGAUGCAUUUGUAUCUCAAACUUUACUUAUUCUGGAAAUAAAUGAAAAGCCAACACCUAUUACAUACCGACAAAAAUGAAAAAAUAAAUAAAUGUAAAGCCAUAGUUCAGUACUGAUGGAAUCUGAGAAAAUUUAUAUGACCGCGAACCCAUAUCUCUGUACUGAAUGUGGGAAAGGCUACACUUGUCUUGCAUCCCUGACCCAGCAUCAGAAAACACAUAUUGGAGAAAAACCUUAUGAAUGUAAAAUAUGUGGUAAGUCCUUUACCCGGAACAGUAAUCUUGUUCAACAUCAAAGAAUACAUACUGGAGAGAAACCUUAUGAAUGUAAUGAAUGUGGGAAAGCUUUUAGUCAGAGCACUAAUCUUAUUCAGCAUCAAAGAGUCCAUACUGGGGAGAAACCUUAUGAGUGUAAUGAAUGUGAAAAAACCUUUAGUCAUAGGUCAUCCCUUAGAAAUCAUGAGAGAAUCCAUACUGGAGAAAAACCCUAUCCUUGUAAUGAAUGUGGGAAAGCUUUCAGCCAUAUCUCUGCCCUUACUCAACAUCAUAGAAUUCAUACUGGAAAGAAACCAUAUGAAUGUACUGAAUGUGGAAAAACCUUCAGCCGCAGCACACACCUAAUUGAACAUCAGGGAAUUCAUUCUGAGGAAAAAUCCUACCAGUGUAAGCAAUGUCGGAAAGUUUUUUGCCACAGUACAUCACUAAUCCGACAUCAGAGAACCCACACAGGAGAGAAACCAUAUGAAUGUAAUGAAUGUGGGAAAGCUUUCAGCCAUACCCCAGCCUUCAUUCAACAUCAAAGAAUUCAUACUGGAGAAAAACCCUAUGAGUGUAAUGCAUGUGGAAAGGCCUUCAAUCGGAGUGCACAUCUUACUGAACACCAGAGAACUCAUACUGGAGAGAAGCCCUAUGUUUGUAAAGAAUGUGGAAAAACCUUCAGUCGAAGUACACACCUUACUGAACAUCUAAAAAUUCAUUCUUGUGUGAAACCCUAUCAAUGUAAUGAAUGUCAGAAACUGUUUUGCUAUAGAACAUCACUAAUUCGACAUCAGAGGACGCAUACAGGAGAGAAACCCUACCAGUGUAAUGAAUGUGGGAAAUCCUUCAGCUUAAGCUCAGCUCUAACUAAACAUAAGCGAAUACAUACAAGGGAGAGACCCUAUCAAUGUACUAAGUGUGGUGAUGUCUUUUGUCAUAGUACAUCCUUAAUUCGACAUCAGAAAACUCAUUUCAGAAAGGAAACCUUAGCAGAGUAAUGAGUGUGGGAAAGCCUGCAGUCAGUCGUAGGUUAUUGUUUACACCUGAGCACUCACAGUUCAAGCAACCCUAGGAUUGUUAUGUGAGGAAAAUCUUAGGCAAAACACUCAUUUACUUAAUAUGCUAUUUGUACUGAGAAGAAGGACUAUGCUUAUAAUCUAAAAAAGGUGUUAUUGAAAGAGAAAGUUAUAAUGGAAGUGUUCAUCCAAAACUGAGGUUUGUUUUUUAAAGACAUUUAGAAAGUUACUUUCAGAGAUAAUUUAUUAAAAUGUAUAUAUUUGCUUAUAAAAAAACUUUUUUUUUUUUUUUUUUUUUUUUUUUUUUUUUUGAGACGGAGUCUCGCUCUGUCGCCCAGGCUGGAGUGCAGUGGCGCGAUCUCGGCUCACUGCAAGCUCCGCCUCCCAGGUUCACGCCAUUCUCCUGCCUCAGCCUCCCGAGUAGCUGGGACUACAGGCGCCCGCUACCACGCCCGGCUAAUUUUUUGUAUUUUUAGUAGAGACGGGGUUUCACCGUGUUAGCCAGGAUGGUCUCGAUCUCCUGACCUCAUGAUCUGCCCGCCUCGGCCUCCCAAAGUGCUGGGAUUACAGGCGUGAGCCACCGCGCCCGGCCAUAAAAAAACCUUUUGAAUUACACAGAAAUCUUAGGUAAGGAAAAUUGUUCACUCUAUAUAUAAUCCCUUUUUUGUUUAUUAAGUCCUAUGUUAUAUUUCAGCAUUCAAGAAACACUUUUAUAGAGGGUUUGAAAAUAAAAUUGACAGAUUUCAUUAAUAGCCAUAGACAAAUAAUGUUUUCUCCCACAAAGAUACUAUGCAUUAUUUUCUAAGAUUUAUGUAAUAUUUUUUAAUGGACUAUAUAUAUGGUUACAAAGAAAAUUGCAAUAAAUUCUCAGAGGGAAAUAUUCAGGCCCUCCCUAAUUUUUUUCAGUGCAAUGCAGUAAAAAUAUAAAUGAAAACAACUAAAAGUAGCACCCCAACAUGAUUUAGAAAUUUAAAAUAAGUUUCUAAGUAAUUUUGGAGUUAAAGAAUAAAUCUGUACAGGAAAAAAAACGUGAUUAUUAGAAGACAAUAAAACUAGAACAAAAAUUAUACAUUGAAUUCAGAAAGGAAAAAGAAUAAUAUAAAUCCAAAGAAAAGAAAUGCUUUAAUAAAGAUAAAACCACACCUCAAUGAAAUAGUUACAAAAGGUAGAUUUCAUAAGGCAAUAGACAAACUUCUAGCAAGUAGGAAUGAUGGGAAAAGGACAAAAAAUCCAAGAGUAAGAAAAUGAUUAUAAAUAUAUAUGGAAGGAAACUUAAAUACUCGAAGUCAAUCAUUAGGAAAUCUAGCAGUUUAGUAAAGUCAGUACUAAGGUUUAUUUUAGAACUUCUAGACUAUUUCAAAAAUAGAAAUCUACAUUAAUAAACAAAAACCUAUCUUAAUAGAUGCUGUAAAAAUCAUUUAAUAAAAUUCUAUAUACAUUGGUGACUUUUUUUAAAGUUAGAAAAUUCCUUAUAUUGUAUAUUGAUGAUGAGCAUGUAUUAGUGUGUGUUCUCCAGAGAGAGAAGAAAGAGAGAAGGAAGAGAAGGAAUGGAGAGAGAGAGAAAGGAAAGUAGGAAAGAGAGAGAGAGGAAGGAAGGGAGGAAAGGGAGAGAAAGGCAGGGAGGAAGGGAGAGAGAGGGAAAGAAGGAAGGAAGAGAGAAAGGAAGGAAGGAGAUGUGUAUGGACAUUAAUGGAUGAUAAGAAGCCCAAGAUCUGCAGUCAGCAAGCUGGAGACUCAGGAGAGCCGAUGGUAAAGUUCUAGUCUUGAGUUUGAGGGCCUGAGUCUUCUGAAGGGCAGGAAAACUGAAGGUGUAAGUUCCAGUUUGAGUCUGCAGGCAGGCAGAAGACUAGUGUCCCAGCUUGAAGACAGGCAGGGAGAGAAGUCUCUUACUCAGCCUUUUAUUCUAUUUGGGCCUACAAUGGAUUGGAUGAGGUCUACAGCCACAUUGAAAUCUGCUUUACUUAGUCUACUGGUUCAAAUGUUAACCUCUUCUUUGAAACACAUUCAAAGACACCUAGAAAAAAUGUUUAUUCAAAUAUCUAAGCACCACAUAUUUGGACCGUCAAGUUGACACAUAAAAUUAACCAUGAUGGGCUAUUUACUAUAAACCUACAAGAAAAACCAUGAAUAACCCAAAGCAUUCUUACCGAAACAGGAAUGAGAUAAAUGAUGUUUGAUGCCACCAUUAUUAGUCAAUAUUAUGCUAAAGAUCCCAGGUAAUCCAAUUAGAGAAAAAAAAGAUAGCAAUAAUUUAAAGGAAGAGAAAAACUGUCAUAAUUUGAAAUACAUUCAAUAUUAGAAAAUCCAAUUAGAACUACUAAAAUGAUAUAUGUACAAAACAAUAUAUUAAAAAAAAGUAGGAGAAAUAGAAAAGAUAGUAGAAAGAAGUGACAUUUACAAUUUUGACAAUCUAAAAAUACCAGGAAUUUAAAAAAUCCAAGAUGUGAUUAGGGAAUAAACCUUUUCUAAAAAAUAUAGAAUAUUAUAAUAAAUGAAAAGAACUGAUUGGGAAAAAUUGGAAAAAUAAUGUAAAGAUGCCAGUUUGUAUUUAAUUUAUCUCUGAUUUGUAAAUUUAAUUGAAUCACAAUAUAAAUGGAAUUUUUAAAAUGACAUCUCUAUUAAGAUAUAAUUCACAAGAAACAGCUGCAGACAGAGGCUCCCACUGAGAAGAAUGAAAACAGUGAGUGAAUCCUGCACUGGUGACUGAGGUAUCCAGGUUCUCCUAUUGGGACUUACUAGGCAAUUGGCAUGACCCAUGGAGAGUGAGGAAAAGCAUGGAGAGUGAGGAAAAGCACGGAGAGUGAGGAAAAGCAGGGUGGUGUGACGGCCCACCUGGAAGCCACACAAGGCAAAGGGAGCUACCACCUGCAGCCAAGGGAGGCAGUGAGUGAUUGUGCUACCCUGCCCAGGAAACCACACUUUUUCCAUGGAUCUGUGCAACCCACAGAUCAGGAGAUCCCCUUCGUGAGCCCACACACCAGGGCCUUGGUGUGUAGCCACAAGGCUAGAGAGAGCCUACCACAGAGCUGUGCAGAUUCUCAGCAGCCACUAGGCUGGAGACUGCCUAAGGCUGCUGAGUUCCUGCGGGAAGGACUGGCCACCAUCACUGUGGCUUCCUGCUGCCUAAGAUGACUUGAGUUCCCGGUAGGAGGAGUGGCAGCCAUCACUGCAGCUCCAGUCUGCCAUUUUUCCCCUGCCAGUGCUGGGGAGACUGGGUAGUUUGGACCCAGGAGGAAUUGCCCACAGCACAGCACAGCAGCUAUAAAAGGUUAUAACCAGACUGUCUCUUUAGGCCAGGCCCUGAUCAAUCCUCCUCACUGGGUGGGGCCUCCCUGCAGGAACUUCAGCAAUUCCUGCCAGGAGUUUAGAAACAGAACUCUGAUCUCUCUGAGACUGAGCUCUUGUGGGGAGGGGUGGCUGUGGUCUCCAUGGAUCAACAGACUUAGUCUUUUCCCCCUGCUGGCUCUGAGGAAUCCGGGCAGUCUGGACGAGUGGGAUUCCACCCAGCAUAGCACACCUCCUCUGCCAAGGGGCAGCUAGAGUGAUUUGUUAGGUGGGUCCUGGAUCCCAUGCCUCCUGACUGGGGAGAUCUCCCCAACAGAGGUCACCAGACACCGUAUACAGGAGCAUUCCUGCUGGCCUUAGUUUGGUGCCCCUCUGAGACAGAAAUCCCAGAGGAAGGAGCAGGCAGCCAUCUUUGCUAUUUUCCAGCCUCCACUGGUGAUACCUCCAAGUAUGGGAGGGACCCCCAGCAAAUUGCAGUAGCCCUAUGGGAGUGGAACCUGACUGUUAAAAGAAAAACAAACAGCAACAGCAACAACAGUAUCAACAAAAAAGUCCCACAAAAAACAUAUCCAAAGGUCAGCAGCCUCAAAGAUCAAAGCUAGAUAAACUCAUGAAAUGAGAAAGAAUCAACAAAAAAGUAACCCCACUGAAAACUCAAAAAGCCAGAGUGCCUCUUCUCCUCCAAUUGAUUGCAACACCUCUCCAGGAAGGACACAGAACUUGGCAGAGGCUGAGGAUGGAUGAAUUGACAGAAGUAGGCUUCAGAAGGUGGGUAAUAACAAACAUUGCUGAGCUAAAGGAGCAUGUUCUAAUCCAAUGGAAAGAAGCUAAGAAUCAUGAUAAAACAUUACAGAAGCUAUUAACCAGAAAAACCAGUAGAGAGGAACAUAAAUGACCUGAUGGAGCGGAAAAACACAACACAAGAACCUCACAAUGAAGCCACAAGUAUCAAUAACCAAAUAGACUGGAGAAAAGAAUUUCAGAGCUUGAAGACUAUCUUGCUGAAAUAAGACGGGCAGACAAGAUUAGAGAAAAAAGAAUGAAAAGGAAUUAACAAAACCUCUGAGAACUAUGGGAUUAUGUAUAAAAGACUGAACCUAUAACUGAUUGGGGUACCUGAGAGAGAAUGGAACCAAGUUGGAAACCAUACUUCAGGAUGUCAUCCAGGAGAACUUCCCCAACCUAACAAGACAAGCCAACGUUCUUAUUCAGGAAGUCCAGAGAACCCCAGUAAGAUAUUCCAUGAGAAGAUCAACCCCAAAACACAUAAUCAUCAGAUUCUCCAAGGUCGAAAUGAAGGAAAAAAUGUUAAAGUCAGCCAGAAAGAAAGGCCAGGUGACCUACAAAGGGGAGCCCAUCAGAAUAACAGCAGACCUCUCAGCAGAAACCCUACAAGCUUGAAGAGGAGGCCAAUAUUCAACAUUCUUAAAGGAAAGAACUUCCAACCCAGAAUUUUACAUACAACCAAACUAAGCUUCGUAAGCAAAGGAGAAAUAAAAUCCUCUUCAGACAAGCAAAUGCUGAGGGAAUUCACUGCCACCAGGCCUCCCUUGCAAGAGCUCCUGAAGGAAGCACUAAAUAUGGAAAGGAAAAAUUAUUUCCAGCCACUCCUAAAACAUGCUGAAGUAUAAAGACCAGUGACACUAUGAAACAACUACAUCAACAAGUCUGCAAAAUAACCAGCUAGCACAAUGAUGACGGGAUCAAAUUCACACAUAACAAUAUUAACUUUAAAUGUAAAUGGGCUAAAUGCCCCCAGUUAAAAGACACAGAAUGGCAAGCUGGAUAAAGAGUCAAGACCUAUCAGUGUGUUGUAUUCAAGAGACUCAUCUCAUAUGCAAAGACACAUAUAGGCUCAAAAUAAAGGGAUGGCAGAAAAUUUACCAAACAAAUGGAAAGCAGAAAAAAGCAGAGGUUGCAAUACUAGUUUCUGACAAAACAGACUUUAAACCAACAAAGAUCAAAAAACACAAAGAAGGGCAUUACAUAAUGGUAAAGGAUUCAAUUCAACAAGAAGAGCUAACUAUUCUAAAUAUAUAUGCACCCAAUACCGGAGCACCCAGACUCAUAAAACAAGUUCUUAGAGACCGACAAAGAGACUUAGAUUCCCACACAAUAACAGUGGGAGACUUUAACAUGCCGCUUUCAAUAUUAGAUCAUCAAGACAGAAAAUUAACAAGAAUAUUCAGGACUUGAACUCACCUCUGGAUCAAGCAGACCUGAUAAUUAUCUACAGAACUCUCCACCAAAAAACAACAGAAUGUACAUUCUUCUCGGUGCCGCAAUGCACUGACUCUAAAAUUGAUCACAUAAUUGGAAGUAAAACACUCUUCAGUAAAUGCAGAAGAACUGAAAUCAUAAAUCACACUCUCUCAGACCACAGCACAAUCAAAUUAGAACACAAGAUUAAGAAACUCACUCAAAACCACACAACUACAUGGAAAUUGAACAACCUUCUCCUGAAUGACUCCUGAGUAAACAAUUAAGGCAGAAAUCAAAUUGUUUUUUGAAACCAAGGAGAACAAAGAGUCAACAUACCAGAAUCUCUGUGAUGCAGCUAAAGCAAUGUUAAAAGGAAAAUUUAUAGCACUAAAUACCCACAUCAGAAGGCUAGAAAGAUCUCAAAUAGACACCCAGCAUCACAACUAAAAAAAUGAGAACCAAGAGCAAACAAACCCAAAGCUAGCAGAAGACAAGAAAUAACCAAGAUCAGAGUGGAUAGAGACACAAAUAACCCUUCAAAAAAAUCAAUGAAUCCAGGAGCUGGUUUUUGAAAAAACUAAUAAAAUAGAUUGCUAACUAGACUAAUGAAGAAAAGAGAGAAGAAUCAAAUAGACACAAUAAAAAAUGGUAAAGGGGAUAUCACCCCGACCCCACAGAAAUACAACCAACCAUCAGAGACUACUAUAAACACUUCUAUGCAAAUAAGCUAGAAAUAUAGAAGAAAUGGAUACAUUCCUGGACACAUACACCCUCCCAAGACUGAACCAGGAAGUUGAACCCCUGAAUAGACCAAUAACGAGUUCUGAAAUUAGGCAAUAAUAAGCUACCAACAACAACAAAAAAAAAGCCCAGGACCAGAUGGAUUUACAGCUGAAUUCUACCACGGGUACAAAGAGAAGCUGGUACCAUUUCUUCUGGAUCUAUUCCAAACAAUUGAAAAGGAGGGACUCCUCACUAACUCAUUUUAUGAGGCCAGCAUCAUCCUGAUAUGAAACCUGGCAGAGAUACAACAAAAAAAGAAAACUUCAGGGCAAUGUCCCUGAUGAACAUCGAUGCAAAAAUUUUCAAUAAAAUACUGGCAAACUGAAUCCAGGAGCACAUCAAAAUGCUUAUCCACUAAUAUCAAAUCAGCUUUAUCCCUGGGAUGCAAGGUUGAUUCAACAUAUGCAAGUCAAUAAAUGUAAUUCAUCACAUAAACAGAACUAAAGACAAAAACCACAUGAUUAUCUCAAUAGAUGCAGAAAAGGACUUUGAUAAAAUUCAACAUCCCUUCAUGUUAAAAACUCUCAAUAAACUAGGUUUUGAUGGAACAUAUCUCAAAAUAGUAAGAGCCACAUGACAAACCCACAGCCAAUAUCAGACUGAAUAGGCAAAACCUGGAAUCUUUCCCCUUGAAAACCAGCACAAGACAAGGAUGUCCUCUAUCACCACUUCUAUUCAACAUGGUAUUGGAAGUUCUGGCCAGGGCAAUCAGUCAAGAGAAAGAAAUAAAGGGUAUUCAAAUAGGAAGAGAGGAAAUCAAACUGUCUCUGUUUGCAGAUGACAUGACCCUAUAUCUAGAAAACUCCAUUGUCUCAGCCCAAAAGCUUCUUAAGCUGAUAAGCAAAUUCAGCAAUGUCUCAGCAUACAAAAUCAAUAUGCAAAAAUCACAAGCAUUCCUAUAUGCCAACAAUAGGCAAGCAGAAAGCCAAAUCAUAAACUCCCAUUCACAAAUGCUACAAAGAGAAUAAAAUACCUAGGAAUACAGAUAACAAGGGAAGUGAAGGACCUCUUCAAGGAGACUACAAACCACUGCUCAAGUAAAUAAGAGAGGACACAAACAAAUGGAAAUACAUUCCAUGAUCAUGGAUGGGAAGAAUCAAUAUCGUGAAAAUGGCCAUGCUGCUCAAAGUAAUUUAUGGAUUCAAUGCUAUUCCCAUUAAACUACCAUUGACAUUCUUCACAGAAUUAGAAAAAACUACUUUAAUGUUCAUAUGGAACCAAAAAAAGCCCAAAUAGCCAAGACAAUCCUAUGCAAAAAGAACAAAGCUGGAGGCAUCACACUACCCAACUCCAAACUAUACUAUGAGGCUACAGUAACCAAACGAGCACAGUACUGGUCCAAAAACGACACAUAGACCAAUGGAACAGAAUAGAGAUCUCAGAAAUAAGACCACACAUCUGGAACCAUCUGACCUUCAACAAACCUGAAAAAACAAGCAAUUGGGAAAGGAGUUCCUAUUUAAUAAGUGGUGCUGGGAGAACUGGCUAGCCAUAUGCAGAAAAUUGAAACUGGACCCCUUCCCUACACCUUAUACAAAAAUGAACUCAAAAUGGAUUAAAGACUUUAAAACCCAAAACUAUAAAUAUCCUAGAAGAAAAUAUAGGCAAUAUCAUUCAGGACAUAGGCACAGGCAAGAUUUCAUGAUGAAAAUGCCAAAAGCUAUUGCAACAAAAGCAAAAAUUGACAAAUGGGAUCUAAUUAAACUAAAGAGCUUCUGUACAGCAAAAGAAACUAUCAUCAGAGUGAACAGAAAAUCUACAGAAUGAGGGAAAACUUUUGCAACCUAUCCAUUUGACAAAGGUCUAAUAUCCAGAGUCUACAAGGAACCUAAACAAAUUUACAAGAACAAAUAAUCCCAUUAAAAAAUAGGCAAAGGACAUGAACAGACACUUCUCAAAAGAAGACAUUUAUGUGGUGAACAAACAUGAAAAAAAAACCAACAUCACUAAUCAUUAGAGAAAUGCAAAUCAAAACCACGAGAUGCCAUCUCAUGCCAGUCAGUAUUAAAAAGGCAAGAAACAACAGAUGCUGUGGAGAGAUAGGAACAGUUUCACGCUGUUGGUAGGAAUAUAAAUUAGUUCAAUCAUUGUGGAAGACAGUGUGGUGAUUCCUCAAAGACCUCAGACCAGAAAUAUCAUUUGACUCAGCAAUCCCAUUACUGAGUAUAUACCCAAAGGAAUAUAAAUCAUUCUAUUAUGAAGAUACAUGCACACGUAUGUUUAUUGCAGCACUAUUCACAAUAGCAAAGACAUGGAAUCAACCCAAAUGCCAAUCAACGAUAGACUGGAUAAAGAAAAUGGAAUGAUAGACUGGAUAAAGAAAACGGAAUAUUAUGCAGCCAUAAAAAGGAAACAGAUCGUGUCCUUUGCAGGGCUGUGGAUGGAGCUGGAAGCCAUUAUCCUCAGCAAACUAACACAGGAACAGAAAACUAAACACUGUGUGUUCUCACUUAUAAGUGGGAGCUGAACAAUGAGAACACAUGGACACAGGGAGAGGAACAAUACACACUGGGGCCUGUUGGGGGUGCAGCAGGAGGAGAGGAUCAGGAUCAAUAGCUAAUACAUGUGAGACUUAAUACCUAGGUGAUGGGUUGAUAGAUGCAGCAAACUACCAUGGCACAUGUUUACUUAUGUAACAAACCUGCAUGUCCUGCACAUGUAUCCUAGAACUUAAAAUUAAAUUUUUUUAAAAGAUACAAUUCA